GCGGCGCGGGUCCUCCAUAUGCUGAGCGCCGGUCCCCUGGGCCCACUUUUCUUUCUCUAUACUUUGUCUCUGUUGUCUUUCUUUUCUCAAGUCUCUCGUUCCACCUGAGGAGAAAUGCCCACAGCUGUGGAGGCGCAGGCCACUCCAUCUGGUGCCCAACGUGGAUGCUUUUCUCUAGGGUGAAGGGACUCUCGAGUGUGGUCAUUGAGGACAAGUCAACGAGAGAUUCCCGAGUACGUCUACAGUGAGCCUUGUGGGUGAAGGUACUCUACAGUGUGGUCAUUGAGGACAAGUUGACGAGAGAGUCCCAAGUACGUCCACGGUCAGCCUUGCGGUAAGCUUGUGUGCUUAGAGGAACCCAGGGUAACGAUGGGGCAAACUGAAAGUAAAUAUGCCUCUUAUCUCAGCUUUAUUAAAAUUCUUUUAAGAAGAGGGGGAGUUAGAGCUUCUACAGAAAAUCUAAUUACGCUAUUUCAAACAAUAGAACAAUUCUGCCCAUGGUUUCCAGAACAGGGAACUUUAGAUCUAAAAGAUUGGGAAAAAAUUGGCAAAGAAUUAAAACAAGCAAAUAGGGAAGGUAAAAUCAUCCCACUUACAGUAUGGAAUGAUUGGGCCAUUAUUAAAGCAACUUUAGAACCAUUUCAAACAGGAGAAGAUAUUGUUUCAGUUUCUGAUGCCCCUAAAAGCUGUGUAACAGAUUGUGAAGAAGAGGCAGGGACAGAAUCCCAGCAAGGAACGGAAAGUUCACAUUGUAAAUAUGUAGCAGAGUCUGUAAUGGCUCAGUCAACGCAAAAUGUUGACUACAGUCAAUUACAGGAGAUAAUAUACCCUGAAUCAUCAAAAUUGGGGGAAGGAGGUCCAGAAUCAUUGGGGCCAUCAGAGCCUAAACCACGAUCGCCAUCAACUCCUCCUCCCGUGGUUCAGAUGCCUGUAACAUUACAACCUCAAACGCAGGUUAGACAAGCACAAACCCCAAGAGAAAAUCAAGUAGAAAGGGACAGAGUCUCUAUCCCGGCAAUGCCAACUCAGAUACAGUAUCCACAAUAUCAGCCGGUAGAAAAUAAGACCCAACCGCUGGUAGUUUAUCAAUACCGGCUGCCAACCGAGCUUCAGUAUCGGCCUCCUUCAGAGGUUCAAUACAGACCUCAAGCGGUGUGUCCUGUGCCAAAUAGCACGGCACCAUACCAGCAACCCACAGCGAUGGCGUCUAAUUCACCAGCAACACAGGACGCGGCGCUGUAUCCUCAGCCGCCCACUGUGAGACUUAAUCCUACAGCAUCACGUAGUGGACAGGGUGGUGCACUGCAUGCAGUCAUUGAUGAAGCCAGAAAACAGGGCGAUCUUGAGGCAUGGCGGUUCCUGGUAAUUUUACAACUGGUACAGGCCGGGGAAGAGACUCAAGUAGGAGCGCCUGCCCGAGCUGAGACUAGAUGUGAACCUUUCACCAUGAAAAUGUUAAAAGAUAUAAAGGAAGGAGUUAAACAAUAUGGAUCCAACUCCCCUUAUAUAAGAACAUUAUUAGAUUCCAUUGCUCAUGGAAAUAGACUUACUCCUUAUGACUGGGAAAUUUUGGCCAAAUCUUCCCUUUCAUCCUCUCAGUAUCUACAGUUUAAAACCUGGUGGAUUGAUGGAGUACAAGAACAGGUACGAAAAAAUCAGGCUACUAAGCCCACUGUUAAUAUAGACGCAGACCAAUUGUUAGGAACAGGUCCAAAUUGGAGCACCAUUAACCAACAAUCAGUGAUGCAGAAUGAGGCUAUUGAACAAGUAAGGGCUAUUUGCCUCAGGGCCUGGGGAAAAAUUCAGGACCCAGGAACAGCUUUCCCUAUUAAUUCAAUUAGACAAGGCUCUAAAGAGCCAUAUCCUGACUUUGUGGCAAGAUUACAAGAUGCUGCUCAAAAGUCUAUUACAGAUGACAAUGCCCGAAAAGUUAUUGUAGAAUUAAUGGCCUAUGAAAAUGCAAAUCCAGAAUGUCAGUCGGCCAUAAAGCCAUUAAAAGGAAAAGUUCCAGCAGGAGUUGAUGUAAUUACAGAAUAUGUGAAGGCUUGUGAUGGGAUUGGAGGAGCUAUGCAUAAGGCAAUGCUAAUGGCUCAAGCAAUGAGGGGGCUCACUCUAGGAGGACAAGUUAGAACAUUUGGGAAAAAAUGUUAUAAUUGUGGUCAAAUCGGUCAUCUGAAAAGGAGUUGCCCAGGCUUAAAUAAACAGAAUAUAAUAAAUCAAGCUAUUAACAGCAAAAAAUAAAAAGCCAUCUGGCCUGUGUCCAAAAUGUGGAAAAGCAAAACAUUGGGCCAAUCAAUGUCAUUCUAAAUUUGAUAAAGAUGGGCAACCAUUGUCUGGAAACAGGAAGAGGGGCCAGCCUCAGGCCCCCCAACAAACUGGGGCAUUCCCAGUUAAACUGUUUGUUCCUCAGGGUUUUCAAGGACAACAACCCCUACAGAAAAUACCACCACUUCAGGGAGUCAGCCAAUUACAACAAUCCAACAGCUGUCCCGCGCCACAGCAGGCAGCACCGCAGUAGAUUUAUGUUCCACCCAAAUGGUCUUUUUACUCCCUGGAAAGCCCCCACAAAAGAUUCCUAGAGGGGUAUAUGGCCCGCUGCCAGAAGGGAGGGUAGGCCUUUGAGGGAGAUCAAGUCUAAAUUUGAAGGGAGUCCAAAUUCAUACUGGGGUAAUUUAUUCAGAUUAUAAAGGGGGAAUUCAGUUAGUGAUCAGCUCCACUGUUCCCCGGAGUGCCAAUCCAGGUGAUAGAAUUGCUCAAUUACUGCUUUUGCCUUAUGUUAAAAUUGGGGAAAACAAAAAGGAAAGAACAGGAGGGUUUGGAAGUACCAACCCUGCAGGAAAAGCUGCUUAUUGGGCUAAUCAGGUCUCAGAGGAUAGACCCGUGUGUACAGUCACUAUUCAGGGAAAGAGUUUGAAGGAUUAGUGGAUACCCAGGCUGAUGUUUCUGUCAUCGGCAUAGGUACUGCCUCAGAAGUGUAUCAAAGUGCCAUGAUUUUACAUUGUCCAGGAUCUGAUAAUCAAGAAAGUACGGUUCAGCCUGUGAUCACUUCAUUCCAAUCAAUUUAUGGGGCCGAGACUUGUUACAACAAUGGCAUGCAGAGAUUACUAUCCCAGCCUCCCUAUACAGCCCCAGGAAUAAAAAAAUCAUGACUAAAAUGGGAUAGCUCCCUAAAAAGGGACUAGGAAAGAAGUCCCAAUUGAGGCUGAAAAAAAUCAAAAAAGAAAAGGAAUAGGGCAUCCUUUUUAGGAGCGGUCACUGUAGAGCCUCCAAAACCCAUUCCAUUAACUUGGGGGAAAAAAAAACAACUGUAUGGUAAAUCAGCAGCGCUUCCAAAACAAAAACUGGAGGCUUUACAUUUAUUAGCAAAGAAACAAUUAGAAAAAGGACAUUGAGCCUUCAUUUUCGCCUUGGAAUUCUGUUUGUAAUUCAGAAAAAAUCCGGCAGAUGGCGUAUAAUGCCGUAAUUCAACCCAUGGGGGCUCUCCCACCCCGGUUGCCCUCUCCAGCCAUGGUCCCCUUUAAUUAUAAUUGAUCUGAAGGAUUGCUUUUUUACCAUUCCUCUGGCAAAACAGGAUUUUGAAAAAUUUGCUUUUACCACACCAGCCUAAAUAAUAAAGAACCAGCCACCAGGUUUCAGUGGAAAGUAUUGCCUCAGGGAAUGCUUAAUAGUUCAACUAUUUGUCAGCUCAAGCUCUGCAACCAGUUAGAGACAAGUUUUCAGACUGUUACAUCGUUCACUAUGUUGAUAUUUUGUGUGCUGCAGAAACGAGAGACAAAUUAAUUGACCGUUACACAUUUCUGCAGACAGAGGUUGCCAACGCGGGACUGACAAUAACAUCUGAUAAGAUUCAAACCUCUACUCCUUUCCGUUACUUGGGAAUGCAGGUAGAGGAAAGGAAAAUUAAACCACAAAAAAUAGAAAUAAGAAAAGACACAUUAAAAGCAUUAAAUGAGUUUCAAAAGUUGCUAGGAGAUACUAAUUGGAUUUGGAGAUAUUAAUUGGAUUUGGCCAACUCUAGGCAUUCCUACUUAUGCCAUGUCAAAUUUGUUCUCUUUCUUAAGAGGGGACUCGGAAUUAAAUAGUGAAAGAACGUUAACUCCAGAGGCAACUAAAGAAAUUAAAUUAAUUGAAGAAAAAAUUCGGUCAGCACAAGUAAAUAGAAUAGAUCACUUGGCCCCACUCCAAAUUUUGAUUUUUGCUACUGCACAUUCCCUAACAGGCAUCAUUGUUCAAAAUACAGAUCUUGUGGAGUGGUCCUUCCUUCCUCACAGUACAAUUAAGACUUUUACAUUGUACUUGGAUCAAAUGGCUACAUUAAUUGGUCAGGGAAGAUUAUGAAUAAUAACAUUGUGUGGAAAUGACCCAGAUAAAAUCACUGUUCCUUUCAACAAGCAACAGGUUAGACAAGCCUUUAUCAAUUCUGGUGCAUGGCAGAUUGGUCUUGCCGAUUUUGUGGGAAUUAUUGACAAUCGUUACCCCAAAACAAAAAUCUUCCAGUUUUUAAAAUUGACUACUUGGAUUUUACCUAAAGUUACCAAACAUAAGCCUUUAAAAAAUGCUCUGGCAGUGUUUACUGAUGGUUCCAGCAAUGGAAAAGUGGCUUACACCGGGCCAAAAGAAUGAGUCAUCAAAACUCAGUAUCACUUGACUCAAAGAGCAGAGUUGGUUGCCGUCAUUACAGUGUUAACAAGAUUUUAAUCAGUCUAUUAACAUUGUAUCAGAUUCUGCAUAUGUAGUACAGGCUACAAAGGAUAUUGAGAGAGCCCUAAUCAAAUACAUUAUGGAUGAUCAGUUAAACCCGCUGUUUAAUUUGUUACAACAAAAUGUAAGAAAAAGAAAUUUCCCAUUUUAUAUUACUCAUAUUCGAGCACACACUAAUUUACCAGGGCCUUUAACUAAAGCAAAUGAACAAGCUGACUUGCUAGUAUCAUCUGCAUUCAUGGAAGCACAAGAACUUCAUGCCUUGACUCAUGUAAAUGCAAUAGGAUUAAAAAAUAAAUUUGAUAUCACAUGGAAACAGACAAAAAAUAUUGUACAACAUUGCACCCAGUGUCAGAUUCUACACCUGGCCACUCAGGAGGCAAGAGUUAAUCCCAGAGGUCUAUGUCCUAAUGUGUUAUGGCAAAUGGAUGUCAUGCACGUACCUUCAUUUGGAAAAUUGUCAUUUGUCCAUGUGACAGUUGAUACUUAUUCACAUUUCAUAUGGGCAACCUGCCAGACAGGAGAAAGUACUUCCCAUGUUAAAAGACAUUUAUUAUCUUGUUUUCCUGUCAUGGGAGUUCCAGAAAAAGUUAAAACAGACAAUGGGCCAGGUUACUGUAGUAAAGCAGUUCAAAAAUUCUUAAAUCAGUGGAAAAUUACACAUACAAUAGGAAUUCUCUAUAAUUCCCAAGGACAGGCCAUAAUUGAAAGAACUAAUAGAACACUCAAAGCUCAAUUGGUUAAACAAAAAAAAGGAAAAGACAGGAGUAUAACACUCCCCAGAUGCAACUUAAUCUAGCACUCUAUACUUUAAAUGUUUUAAACAUUUAUAGAAAUCAGACCACUACCUCUGCAGAACAACAUCUUACUGGUAAAAGGAACAGCCCACAUGAAGGAAAACUGAUUUGGUGGAAAGAUAAUAAAAAUAAAACAUGGGAAAUGGGGAAGGUGAUAACGUGGGGGAGAGGUUUUGCUUGUGUUUCACCAGGAGAAAAUCAGCUUCCUGUUUGGAUACCCACUAGACAUUUAAAGUUCUACAAUGAACUCACUGGAGAUGCAAAGAAAAGUGUGGAGAUGGAGACACCCCAAUCGACUCGCCAGGUAAACAAAAUGGUGAUAUCAGAAGAACAGAAAAAGUUGCCUUCCAUCAAGGAAGCAGAGUUGCCAAUAUAGGCACAAUUAAAGAAGCUGACACAGUUAGCUAAAAAAAAAAGCCUAGAGAAUACAAAGGUGACACCAACUCCAGAGAAUAUGCUGCUUGCAGCUCUGAUGAUUGUAUCAACGGUGGUAAGUCUUCCCAAGUCUGCAGGAGCAGCUGCAGCUAAUUAUACUUACUGGGCCUAUGUGCCUUUCCCACCCUUAAUUCGGGCAGUUACAUAGAUGGAUAAUCCUAUUGAAGUAGAUGUUAAUAAUAGUGCAUGGGUGCCUGGCCCCACAGAUGACUGUUGCCCUGCCCAACCUGAAGAAGGAAUGAUGAUGAAUAUUUCCAUUGGGUAUCCUUAUCCUCCUGUUUGCCUAGGGAAGGCACCAGGAUGCUUAAUGCCUACAACCCAAAAUUGGUUGGUAGAAGUACCUACAGUCAGUGCUACCAGUAGAUUUACUUAUCACAUGGUAAGUGGAAUGUCACAGAUAAAUAAUUUACAGGACCCUUCUUAUCAAAGAUCAUUACAAUGUAGGCCUAAGGGGAAGGCUUGCCCCAAGGAAAUUCCCAAAGAAUCAAAAAGCCCAGAAGUCUUAGUCUGCGGAGAAUGUGUGGCUGAUACUGCAGUGUAGUACAAAACAAUGAAUUUUGAACUAUGAUAGACUGGGUCCCUUGAGGCCAAUUAUAUCAUAACUGUACAGGCCAGACUCAUUCAUGUUCACAGGCCCCAUCCAUCUGGCCCAUUAAUCCAGCCUAUGACGGUGAUGUAACUGAAAGGCUGGACCAGGUUUAUAGAAGGUUAGAAUCACUCUGUCCAAGGAAAUGGGGUGAAAAGGGAAUUUCAUCACCUUGACCAAAGUUAGUCCUGUUACUGGUCCUGAACAUCCAGAAUUAGGAAGCUUACUGUGGCCUCACACCACAUUAGAAUUUGUUCUGGAAAUCAAGCUAUAGGAACAAGAGAUCGUAAGUCAUAUUAUACUAUCAACCUAAAUUCCAGUCUGACAAUUCCUUUGCAAAAUUGUGUAAAACUCCCUUAUAUUGCUAGUUGUAGGAAAAACAUAGUUAUUAAACCUGAUUCCCAAACCAUAAUCUGUGAAAAUUGUGGAAUGUUUACUUGCAUUGAUUUGACUUUUAAUUGGCAGCACCGUAUUCUACUAGGAAGAGCAAGAGAGGGUGUGUGGAUCCUUGUGUCCAUGGACCGACCAUGGGAGGCUUCGCUAUCCAUCCAUAUUUUAACGGAAGUAUUAAAAGGAAUUCUAACUAGAUCCAAAAGAUUCAUUUUUACUUUGAUGGCAGUGAUUAUGGGCCUCAUUGCAGUCACAGCUACUGCUGCGGCUGCUGGAAUUGCUUUACACUCCUCUGUUCAAACUGCAGAAUACGUAAAUGAUUGGCAAAAGAAUUCCUCAAAAUUGUGGAAUUCUCAGAUCCAAAUAGAUCAAAAAUUGGCAAACCAAAUUAAUGAUCUUAGACAAACUGUCAUUUGGAUGGGAGAGGCUCAUGAGCUUGGAAUAUCUUUUUCAGUUACGAUGUGACUGGAAUACAUCAGAUUUUUGUGUUACACCACAAGCCUAUAAUGAGUCUGAGCAUCACUGGGACAUGGUUAGAUGCCAUCUGCAAGGAGGAGAAGAUAAUCUUACUUUAGACAUUUCAAAAUUAAAAGAAUUUUUUUUUUCUUUGAGACAGAGUCUCGCUCUGUCGCCCAGGCUGGAGUGCAGUGGCGUGAUCUCAGCUCACUGCAAGUUCCGCCUCCUGGGUUUACACCAUUCUCCUGCCUCAGCCUCCCAAGUAGUUGGGACUACAGGAGCCCACCACCAUGCCUGGCUAAUUUUUUUUGGGUUUUUAAUAGAGAUGGAGUUUCACCGUGUUAGCCAGGAUGGUCUCGAUCUCCUGACCUUGUGAUCUGCCCACCUUGGCCUCCCAAAGUGCUGGGAUUACAGUCGUGAGCCACCGUGCCCAGCCAAGAAAAAAUUUUUGAGGCAUCAAAAGCCCAUUUAAAUUUGGUGCCAGGAACGGAGACAAUCGUGAAAGCUGCUGAUAGCCUCACAAAUCUUAAGCCAGUCACUUGGGUUAAAAGCAUCAGAAGUUUCACUAUUGUAAAUUUCAUAUUAAUCCUUGUAUGCCUGUUCUGUCUGUUGUUAGUCUACAGGUGUAUCCAGCAGCUCCAAAGAGACAGCAACCAGCAAGAAUGGGCCAUAGUGACGAUGGUGGUUUUGUCAAAAAGAAAAGGGGGGGAUAUGUAAGGAAAAGAGAGAUCAGACUUUCACUGUGUCUAUGUAGAAAAGGAAGACAUAAGAAACUCCAUUUUGAUCUGUACUAAGAAAAAUUGUUUUGCCUUGAGAUGCUGUUAAUCUGUAACUUUAGCCCCAACCCUGUGCUCACGGAAACAUGUGCUGUAAGGUUUAAGGGAUCUAGGGCUGUGCAGGAUGUACCUUGUUAACAAUAUGUUUGCAGGCAGUAUGUUUGGUAAAAGUCAUCGCCAUUCUCCAUUCUCGAUUAACCAGGGGCUCAAUGCACUGUGGAAAGCCACAGGAACCUCUGCCCAAGAAAGCCUGGCUGUUGUGGGAAGUCAGGGACCCCGAAUGGAGGGACCAGCUGGUGCUGCAUCAGGAAACAUAAAUUGUGAAGAUUUCUUGGACAUUUAUCAGUUUCCAAAAUUAAUACUUUUAUAAUUUCUUACACCUGUCUUACUUUAAUCUCUUAAUCCUGUUAUCUUUGUAAGCUGAGGAUAUACGUCACCUCAGGACCACUAUUGUACAAAUUGAUUGUAAAACAUGUUCACAUGUGUUUGAACAAUAUGAAAUCAGUGCACCUUGAAAAUGAACAGAAUAACAGUGAUUUUAGGGAACAAAGGAAGACAACCAUAAGGUCUGACUGCCUGAGGGGUCGGGCAAAAAGCCAUAUUUUUCUUCUUGCAGAGAGCCUAUAAAUGGACGUGCAAGUAGGAGAGAUAUUGCUAAAUUCUUUUCCUAGCAAGGAAUAUAAUACUAAGACCCUAGGGAAAGAAUUGCAUUCCUGGGGGGAGGUCUAUAAACGGCCGCUCUGGGAGUGUCUGUCCUAUGUGGUUGAGAUAAGGACUGAGAUACGCCCUGGUCUCCUGCAGUACCCUCAGGCUUACUAGGAUUGGGAAACCCCAGUCCUGGUAAAUUUGAGGUCAGGCCGGUUCUUUGCUCUGAACCCUGUUUUCUGUUAAGAUGUUUAUCAAGACAAUACAUGCACCGCUGAACAUAGACCCUUAUCAGGAGUUUCUGAUUUUGCUCUGGUCCUGUUUCUUCAGAAGCAUGUCAUCUUUGCUCUGCCUUCUGCCCUUUGAAGCAUGUGAUCUUUGUGACCUACUCCCUGUUCAUACACCCCUCCCCUUUUAAAAUCCCUAAUAAAAACUUGCUGGUUUUGUGGCUCAGGGGGGCAUCAUGGACCUACCAAUACGUGAUGUCACCCCCGGUGGCCCAGCUGUAAAAUUCC